ACUCUCAAGCGCGCCGCGAAAGGAGGGAGCAGCUUCCGGGACCUGGCGCGGCUUUUGUGUUGGGCAGCGCGAAUGUGGCGAGCUCGGUGCGUCUCCGCUGCUCCUUCCCCUUAUCCCUGGGAGGUCCAAGUGGUCCCGCGGCAGCUUCUGUUGCUCUGGGACCUGCAGGUCCCGGAAGGUCCUUAGGGAGGACCCCAGACACCGGAGACUGGGAAAUGGAUUCAGUGUCAUUUGAAGAUGUGGCUGUGGCCUUUACUCAGGAGGAGUGGGCUUUGCUGGAUCCUUCUCAAAAGAAUCUCUACAGAGAUGUGAUGCAAGAAAUCUUCAGGAACCUGGCUUCUGUAGGAAACAAAUCAGAAGACCAGAAUAUCCAAGAUGACUUCAAAAAUCCUGGGAGAAAUCUAAGCAGUCAUGUGGUAGAGAGACUGUUUGAAAUUAAAGAAGGCAGUCAAUAUGGAGAAACCUUCAGCCAGGAUUCAAAUUUGAAUCUGAAUAAGAAAGUUUCUACUGGAGUAAAGCCAUGUGAAUGCAGUGUGUGUGGAAAAGUCUUCAUAUGUCAUUCAGCCCUUCAUAGGCACAUCCUGUCUCACAUUGGAAACAAACUAUUUGAGUGUGAGGAAUGUCCAGAGAAGUUAUAUCAUUGCAAACAAUGUGGGAAAGCCUUUAUCUCUCUCACCAGUGUUGACAGACACAUGGUAACACACACUAGUAAUGGGCCUUAUAAGGGUCCAGUGUAUGAGAAGCCUUUUGAUUUUCCUAGUGUAUUUCAAAUGCCUCAGAGCACUUACACUGGAGAGAAAACAUAUAAAUGUAAACAUUGUGAUAAAGCCUUCAAUUAUUCAAGUUAUCUUCGUGAACAUGAAAGAACUCAUACUGGAGAGAAACCCUAUGCAUGUAAGAAAUGUGGUAAAUCAUUCACUUUUUCCAGUUCUCUUCGCCAACAUGAAAGAUCUCAUACUGGAGAGAAACCCUAUGAAUGUAAGGAAUGUGGCAAAGCCUUCAGUCGUUCCACUUACUUGGGAAUACAUGAAAGAACGCAUACUGGAGAAAAACCCUAUGAAUGUAUAAAAUGUGGCAAAGCCUUUAGAUGUUCCAGAGUCCUCAGAGUCCAUGAAAGGACUCACAGUGGAGAAAAGCCCUAUGAAUGUAAACAAUGUGGUAAAGCCUUCAAAUAUUCUAGUAACCUAUGUGAGCAUGAAAGAACUCACACUGGAGUGAAACCUUAUGGAUGUAAGGAAUGUGGUAAGUCGUUUACUUCUUCCAGUGCCCUUCGAAGCCAUGAAAGGACUCAUACUGGAGAAAAACCCUAUGAAUGUAAGAAAUGUGGUAAAGCCUUCAGUUGUUCCAGUUCCCUUCGAAAGCAUGAAAGAGCUUAUAUGUGGUAAAAAACAACAACAACAAAACACCUCUGUCAAUGUAAGAAGUGUGUUAAAGCUUUCAGUUAUUCUAGUUUCAUUAGAACACGUGAAAAAAUUAAAAACUCAAAUUAGAGAGAAACCCAACACAUGUAAGGAAGAUUAGAAUGUAUGCAAUUUUCCUAGUUCCCUUCUAAAACUUAGAAGGACCCGUCCUGGGAAAGAACGUCAUAAAAUACGAAAAAUGUGUUAGAACACUUUAUUUUCCCAGCCGCUUUCAAAUAUAUUUUUAUCAGUGGUUCAUUGUUAAAGAAGGUGUCUAUACUUUAGAUUUUCAGUUUUUUGCAGGGAAUCAUGGAGCUGAGAAUUUCACAGAUACUUUAUAAGCCAUAGUACAUGAGCUUAAUAGGCUGUGUUUUGUUUCUCAUCAGUUAACAUAAUUUUUGUCUAUUCAUUUAAAAAUUUGUUGGAUCCCUAGACUAAGUUGAAAUGUAUUUCUAAUAGUAGGCAAUUUUAAUUUUCAUGUAGUUGUUUAAUUGUUCUCUAAUUAAUGGACCAAUGAAAAAUGAGUUCAUGUGUGUGUGUGUGUGUGUGUGUGUGUGUGUGUAUUCUACCUUUUUAUGGGAAAACUACUUUUUUGUUGUAAAGAUUUUCUUCUGUUUUCUUUGCUAAUAAAGAAUUGUUAUUAAUUUGCAUGUAUGUGAAGUUUAUAUAGUCUCAUGUACAUUGUUAUUUUCAUUUUCUUUCCUUUAUUCUGUCAUGAGUUUUGGCUGUUACUUGCAUAGUUCACUUUUUUAAAAAAUGUUAUGUUUUUAGAGAGGGUCUCACUUUGUCAGCUAGGCUGAAGUGUAGUGGUAAUAAUAGUCUUAGCUCACUGCAGCCUCAAAUUCCUGGGCUCAAGUGAUUCUCCCACCUUAGCCUCCUAUGUAGCUGGAGCUACAGACACAUGCCACCAUGCUCAGCUAAUUAUAUAAUUUUAAAAAUUUUUUAUAGAGAUGGGAUCUCGCUGUAUUGUCUAGGCUGGUAUUGAAUUCCUGGCCUCAAGCUAUCCUCCUGCCUCAGCCUGUCUACAUGUUGGGGUUACUGACAUGAGCUACCACACCUGGCCCACUUUUUACUUUGAAUUAAGAAGAGAGAACUGUGAUUGGACAGUAUGCUUGUCUAAUCUGCGUGUGAAAGCAUUCAGUCUCACCAUCAAGUAUAUUGUGGAUUUUUCAUAAAUAUUCUCAAACAGGCUCAGGAAGUUUUCUUGUGUUUUUUAUUUAUUGUUUCAUGGUAAAGGAGUGUUGAACUCUUAUGACAUGUUUUUUUCUGCAUCUAUUGAGAUGAUUUGUGGUUUUUGGCAUUCUACUGAUAGUCUAUUACGUUAACUGGCUUUCAGAUAUAAAUAUAUUAUGGUUAUCUGGGUGAAAUUUGUCUUCAUCAUGGAAUAUAAGUAUUUUAUCUACAGGUUGAACAUCUGUAAACCCCAGAUUCCAAUACCAAAUCUGAAAUGCUCCGAAGUCAAAAACUGUUUGAGCACCAGUCUUAUGCUCAACAGAAAUGCUCAUUAGAGGAUUUUUGAUAUUUGGAUUAGGGAUGCUCAUCCAGUAAGUUUUCUGCAAAUAUUCCAAAAUGUUAAAAGUCUGAAAUCCAAAGCACUUCCGUUCCCAAGUAUUUCAGAUAAGAAACACUCAACCCAUAUUGAUAACGUUCAAUUUUCCAGUGUAUUGUUGGGGCCUUUUGCAUUUAUAGUCAAAUUGGUGUGCCCUAGUAUACCAUAUAGUAUAGCAUCAUCUGUAUAUAUAGCAUGUCUACAUGUAUACUUAUAUGUGUAUAAGUAGCUAUAUAAUAUGUGGUAUAGUACAGUUUUGUAAGUUACUAUGAAUUAUGCAUAACUAGUUUAUAUUAUGUGUAAUUAGCACUACAAUAAAUUGUAUAUUACAGGAUUAUGGCAUUAUAACAUACUAUUUUGAUCUUAUCAGUCUGUAGCCUAACAUAUUUCAGUUGCCUACCAUUCCACAGAUGCAUUUAAACAAACCAAUUGCAUCCUUAUGAGAACCAAGAAGCAUCUCACGUUCUUGAUACUACAAAGCAUUCCCCUUACACCCUGUUUGUUCUAUCUGCUCCGUAGUGCAAGUCUUGUGUGGACCAGCCUCGUUUACAGAACCCUCCCUUUUUUGUCUAUGAAUGUAUGUAACUAAUAACUUCUCUCAAUCUUAUCUGUACACUCAUGGGUGUCACGUGUUUUUCCCAGUAGUCUUAGGGUCCUAAUUUUUCCUGUCACCCAUGAGACUGUGAAAACAAUUGGCAUUACCAACAGAAUGAACCAACCAUGACUGAUGAUAUCUUUUCAGCUUUAACUACCUGCUUUUGUCUAACUGGUUCCAUAAUAUAACAGAAGUCACCUGAAUUAGAAACAGCAAUUGAUGGUGGACUUUCACUUUGGUCUACACAGUGCUUUGUGUUAUCAGCUGUUGCCACCUCUUCCCACAGUAGAACUCUCAACUCCUAGACAUGACUGGUUGACCAGCCGUUCCCCAGGAGGAUGUAUGUUCCACCUUGACCUGUGUUUGGCAGGCAGUUUCCAAGGUACCCCACAUUGAGGCAGUGACCCAGCACCUUCACCACUGGGUUCUUUAUUCCUGAUUAUCAAAAGUCAGACUACUGCUCUGUGGUAACUGCAUCUCGUUUGGUUGCCAUCACUGGAUGCUUGGAGUAGCCAUGUGAACGUUAUUACUGUACACACUUGGGACAGCUCCAGGGAUUUUGUGUGUGUGAAGUUGCAGAAAGGAAGAAUGUCCCCAUGCUGGGGAGAAUUAAGCAUGUCACCUAAUUGUGUAACAAGAUGACUUGUGCAAGA